AUCAGAUUCUCAAUCUUGCUUGAAGACUGACAAGAUGUCCCUGUGGACUCCCAAACUCUACUCCAGAUGGGGAGGUGCCCUUAACACCAAGAUUUUAAAAGCUCCAAUUUCAGAGCAAGAGUCGAAAACUCACAGAUAAAGUUAUAGUUAUUUCAGGGUUCUGAAAAGACGCAGAACAUGAAGGGACUCAGAAGUCUGGCAGCAACAACCUUGGCUCUUUUCCUGGUGUUUGUUUUCCUGGGAAACUCCAGCUGCGCUCCGCAGAGACUGUUGGAGAGAAGGAACUGGACUCCUCAAGCUAUGCUCUACCUGAAAGGGGCACAGGGUCGCCGCUUCAUCUCCGACCAGAGCCGGAGAAAGGACCUCUCCGACCGGCCACUGCCGGAAAGACGAAGCCCAAAUCCCCAACUACUAACUAUUCCGGAGGCAGCAACCAUCUUACUGGCGUCCCUUCAGAAAUCACCAGAAGAUGAAGAAAAAAACUUUGAUCAAACCAGAUUCCUGGAAGACAGUCUGCUUAACUGGUGAAAAUAUACUGGAUUAUGUUUAAUUAUGGUUCUAUUCUCUUUGAAAACAUGAACCAUGUGAAUAAAACCUUUGGACCCUUUUAUUCCAUUUGUAAUCUUAAGAACACACACAGAUAGUUUUAUUCUUUCAGAAACAAAAUAUAUAUAGGAUGCUUAGCUGAGAACAUCAUCUUCUUUCAUUGCUUCAGGUCCUGUUUAGAUGACCAAAAAUGUUUUCAGAUCACCUUGUGUCUUACUCUUGAGUUUCUUAGAAUAUUUAUAAUUAUAAGGCUGAAGACUAAAGUGUUCUUUCCUUUUAACUAUAGCCAGUACCUGUCUUGAUCUUAGUUGUGUUUUUUUUUCAUUUUGUUACCCACUUGCAUUUUGUUUUCACUCAGCAGAAAUUCUCCUUCUCUGUUUUCCUUUUAUCCCAUCCCCAAGAAUGUGGAAGGAAGGUGAGAAACAUGGCAGGAUGGGAAAUAGGAGAGUAUGACUCUCUAUAGCUCAUCCAGGAGUAAUCAAUUAAGAAGAUAAAUUGGAUGACUGUGGAGAAGCUCUGUGAUAGGAACACUUCAGUGUGGUUGCUGAGAGGAGACAGUCAUUGAGGUAGAAGGUUUGCCAAAGAUCCAGAGCUCAGAGCUCCCUUUGUGCUCUUUGGGAAUUACCUUGCAUUCAGUUUAGAAACAUGGAUCUAAAAGUUACUGGGAAAUAAGCAGAUGGAGACACACUCUGUUGUUUACGUAUUGGAAGAAGGGAACAAGCCAGUUUUGUUAGAGGUAACUCAUUUUCCAUGACCAAACAGACUCAACAGAUUCAAGUACUCUGCUUACUCUAAUUGACUAGACUCUAGGUUUUAUUUGACAUCAUAGCAUUACAUAAAUCACUCUGAUAACAUAAGUGCACAGUAAUAUGCCUGAUCUCUUCCUUUUUAAAAGCCAACUUGAGUUCAGUACCAUCUGAAUACACACACAUGCACAUAUACCCACACACGCAUACACACAUACUCCUGUGGCAAACAUAAUAAUGUAUUUAUUUAGAAUUAUAAUAUGACCAUCAUGUUAAUUAUUUUUUACCUAAUCAGAGUUGUUAUUGACAAAUGUCAUAAGUGGAAAGUAUUAAUUCUUAUUGUCAUCAGUAUUUAGCCAUUAUUUAGUAGCUCAAGAAUAUCUUUAUGUGAAUGUCUCUGUAACUUGGAAUUGCAAUUUCACUGUGUUAAGUAAUCAGAACUCUGCUUAUAAGAUUUAUCUGUAUCUUGUUUCAUAAUUUAAUAAUGAAACUAAAUUCAAGUUAAUGUAAUGUUGAUCUCCGUCGAAAAAUAACUUGUGAGCAUUAAAAUAUCUGUAUGGCAUUAUAAUAGGCACCUGUCAUUAAUUAUGAUUUGAUUUGAAAGUAGACUUACUAGGUAGUGCUUACAUCUGAUUUAUUGAAAAUUUUUUCCAAAAGCAUUGUCUUUUAUUUAUACAGUCCUAACCACUUCACCAUUAGGAGGGGUGGGACAUUAAAAAUUAUUUACCCAUCAGACAUAAAAUUGUACAAAUUGACUAUUCAAAAUAGUAUGUGUAUUCAAAGAACACUUUUAACAUCUAUCUUAUGAAAUAAUUCUUCCUACAACUAACCAGAACAAUCUCAAAAAUGUCAUACUAACCAUUGUUUUAAAAGCUGUCUCAAUGAUCAAUAGCUGUUAAAAUAUAGCUCCAAGUAUUCUAAGUACUCAAAUUCCUUGAAUGUUCUUAUGUACAAAUAUGCUGAUUAAUUAAAAGGUCCCUCUUCCCAA